AGUUCCGUUCCUGCUCCGCUUGAGGAGAAGCGCCAAGUGCGCAUGGGGACGCUAUAGCAAUUCGUUUGCUGUCCUUCCUCUCCUUCGAAGAUGACAAGGCCUACCAUCGUUUCUUCCUGCCUUUGGGCCGUCAGGCAGUUGGUUGGGACCCGCUCCAACCCUCGGUUCUUCCUGCAAUACAGUGGAUACAAUUUGUCAUGGCUACUCUGAGUGUUAUAGGUUCAAGUUCACUUAUUGCCUAUGCUGUAUUCCAUAAUAUACAGAAAUCUCCAGAGAUAAGACCACUUUUUUAUCUGAGCUUCUGUGACCUGCUCCUGGGACUUUGCUGGCUCACGGAGACACUUCUCUAUGGAGCUUCAGUAGCAAAUAAGGACAUCAUCUGCUAUAACCUACAAGCAGUUGGACAGUUCUGGAGGCUGGAAGGUCCAAGAUUAAGAUAAUCAGCAGAUCUGGUGUCUGGGGAGACGGGGUUUCGCCAUGUUUGCCAGGCUGGUCCUGAAUGCCUGACCUCAAGUGAUUCACCGCUUGGGCCUCCCAAAGUGCUGGGAUUACAGGUGUGAGCCACUGCACCUGGCCUCCUUAAAUGUAUCUUUAUGGCCUAAUUUUCACCUUUGCACCCAGUUGAUAUUCUACAUUUCCUCAUUUCUCUACACCGUCAAUUACAUCUGGUAUUUGUACACAGAGCUGAGGAUGAAACACACCCAGAGUGGACAGAGCACAUCUCCACUGGUGAUAGAUUAUACUUGUCGAGUUUGUCAAAUGGCCUUUGUUUUCUCAAGCCUGAUACCUCUGCUAUUGAUGACACCUGUAUUCUGUCUGGGAAAUACUAGUGAAUGUUUCCAAAACUUCAGUCAGAGCCACAAGUGUAUCUUGAUGCACUCACCACCAUCAGCCAUGGCUGAACUUCCACCUUCUGCCAACACAUCUGUCUGUAGCACACUUUAUUUUUAUGGUAUCGCCAUUUUCCUGGGCAGCUUUGUACUCAGCCUCCUUACCAUUAUGGUCUUACUUAUCCGAGCCCAGACAUUGUAUAAGAAGUUUGUGAAGUCAACUGGCUUUCUGGGGAGUGAACAGUGGGCAGUGAUUCACAUUGUGGACCAACGGGUGCGCUUCUACCCAGUGGCCUUCUUUUGCUGCUGGGGCCCAGCUGUCAUUCUAAUGAUCAUAAAGCUGACUAAGCCACAGGACACCAAGCUUCACAUGGCCCUUUAUGUUCUCCAGGCUCUAACGGCAACAUCUCAGGGUCUACUCAACUGUGGAGUAUAUGGCUGGACGCAGCACAAAUUCCACCAACUAAAGCAGGAGGCUCGGCGUGAUGCAGAUACCCAGACACCAUUAUUAUGCUCACAGAAGAGAUUCUAUAGCAGGGGCUUAAAUUCACUGGAAUCCACCCUGACUUUUCCUGCCAGUACUUCUACCAUUUUUUGAAACUACAAUACUGGAACAUCCAGGAACUGGAGUUAUUCUACGCUAAUGGAUUGGAAAGAAUGUUGGGAAAGGACAUCUUAAAUCUUUUCUAACUAUGCCCUAAACUGCAGAACUCAAAGGAAAUAUAGUGCCAUUGUUAGUAGUCAUUCUAGAUGAAUUGGGAGUAUCUCUCCAGUUAUUCCCAGAUUCACUAGUGAUCCUUAAAGUCUCUAUUCAGGGAGAGGAAGACACUUUCCAUCUCAGAGAUAGACUCGUGUUACCUUGAUGGAUAUUGGAUUUGUCUAAGUCUCUUCUAGAAAAAAUAAAUUCUAGAUUAUUAUUUA